GAGCUUCCUGGCUCCUUUGUUUACCUAAGCAAGCCUGGGCAAUGGCGGGCGCCCCUCCCCCAGCCUCGCUGCCGCCUUGCAGUUUGAUCUCAGACUGCUGUGCUAGCAAACAGCGAGACUCCGUGGGCGUAGGACCCUCCGAGCCAGGUGUGGGAUAUAGUCCCGUGGUGCGCCGUGUUUUAAGCCGGUCUGAAAAGCGCAAUAUUCGGGUGGGAGCGACCCGAUUUUCCAGGUGCGUCCGUCACCCCUUUCUUUGACUCGGAAAGGGAACUCCCUGACCCCUUGCGCUUCCCAGGUGAGGCAAUGCCUCGCCCUGCUUCGGCUCUCGCACGGUGCGUGCACCCACUGGCCUGCGCCCACUGUCUGGCACUCCCUAGUGAGAUGAACCCGGUACCUCAGAUGGAAAUGCAGAAAUCACCCGUCUUCUGCGUCGCUCACGCUGGGAGCUGUAGACCGGAGCUGUUCCUAUUCGGCCAUCUUGGCUCCUCCCCGAUAGUUAAGGUAUUUGAAUGCUUCCUAUGAGAUACUAUAUCUGAACAACUCUUAUUCUAAUUUUAUAGAUGAGGAUGAAUAAUUUGCAGAAGACCACACAGCUUAUAUUAAUGCAAAUGUUAGUAUUUUAUUUUCUCAUCUGAAAUAUGUGAAAAUAACAAACUAAGGAGAGUUCUUAAUAAUAAACACAAAAUGUUGGUAGUAAUUACUAGAUUUUCUGUUAUAUCUCCAUUUACGUUUAUUGUUGCCUCAGUCCCUGACCAUGUUUUGCAAAAUAUGUUGCAGAAUGAUUUUCAUUCUUCAGGAUGGCUAGAUUGGGUGGCUGUAUGCAGCUUCUUGUAUUUCCAAACACAGGGAACCUGUAUCAAGCUUGGGCCCAUGCUGCCUUAUUCUAUCUUUAAACUUUUAGAGAACCCAGAAUUAGCUUGAAUGAGUCUAGACACAAACCAUCAACCAGCGGCAUGUUUCCAUAAUAUUAACCAUUUACUUUGAGUUUUGUAGGUGUUGCCUGCUUACGGGAAUAUUUGAGCUUGGUCUCUAAUCAUAUUUGAUACAUAUUUUUACAAAUCUCUUAUGUGACUAAAAUGUUCAGUUUAAAAUGUAUAUACCUUUAAGCAUGAAACAUAAAGUUUGGUUGGUAAUGGACUCAAUAAUGUGUUCCAAAUAUCUGCAUAGUGCUAAAAAUGAAAAUAUUGGAAUUGUGUAAUUUGGCAAAUUGAAAAUACUAAUAAAUCCUACUGUAGGAUGUCCAUGAAAGAAAUGCGUUUCCCUUAAACUUAUCCUGACAAAAGAGAAACAUAUAAUAAGAUGAUGAUCCACUAAACAACUGAACAUGCAAGCAUGAAUUGUAGAAUCUUAAGGAAACCAGUAAUUCCCUCACACUCUACAGAGGAAAUAAUUUCUCUACAGAGAAAUAAUUUUUUUGUUCUUUUUAAUUUUUUUCCUUGCUUGAUUUUAGUCUUCCUUGUAAGGAAAAAGCUCGUUUUCUGGAGGGACCUUGCCGAAGCAAGACCUUUUGAUGGUGUGGUCAGAAAGAGAGCAAAUCUUUCCUUUUUAUUAAAAAGUAUUGGCUAAUGAACUUCUUCAUCUUUUGGCUUUUCCCCAGCUUAUUUGGAUUCCUCAGUUUAACUUCCAUUUCUCUUAAAGCACAACAAAAACAUUCUAGUUGUUAGGACAUCUACCUUAAAUGCUAGGAAGAUGUUCAAGUUUUUAACUCCUAAGAAUAAAAGAUGACAUAGCAGGGAAGAGCUAAACUAGGAGCUAAUGAAGUCUGUUUAUUCUAUAUUAAGACAUUUCUAAAUGCAAAAGCUUUACAGUAAGAAACUGAUUAUCUAUGAAAAAAUCUUUUUUUUGUGAAAGGAAGAGUUCUAGGAAAGCAGAUAAAUUUACAACCAAAUUGAAGGGUAAUAAUAGCAAAAUCAUGGGAUUAUGUUAAGCUAAAAAAUAAGUAAAUGAAAAACUAACAUGAUUGGUGGUGAAGUAUGGAUUGUUGUAAUGAAUAUUUAUUUUGAGUUUCUUAUCCUAUAUUAUUUUUAGAGGACUGCAUAUAUGAUAAUUAUUGCUGUCUUUGGUGUCCAGCCAGUUCAUACCUUCAUCUUUCAACAGCACAUUUGAGUUGCAUGUUAUUCUUUACAUAGAACUAAAUAUAUCCUGAUUUGCAAUACAUUUCCUAUUGCGGAAAUGUUACAAAAUUAUUCAGUGACGGCAGUAAUUCUUAUAUUAUAAACUCGUUUUAUUUUAUUUAACAUAUAUUAAAUGCCAGACAUUAUUCUGACCACUUAUUUUUUACUCAUGUCAUGUGAUAAUUGAAUAUUUGUAUACUGCUUUAAACCUUAAAAAAGUAAAGAAACUUCAUAGAUUUGUAGAGUUCUGUGCCAUUUUUUUCUCUUAUUAGCUUUUCUAUUACCAAUCAACACAUUUAAUCUCUUUCCUGCUACCCACGCUAAUGUGUUAAAACACUUCAUACUUCCUGCAAAUAUUCUUUUCUUUUUAAAAAUUUUUUAAAAAUAUUUAAAAAGUUGUUUGCUCACUCUACAUUUUGGAUUAUUUACUUCAGUAGAUUCCCAAAAUUUGCAAAGAUGAUUUCAACUGCAAAUAAAUCAUUCCAUUCUCUUUUUCACCUUUUAAAACGUUUAUUCAAUAUUAACAGCCAAUUCUGCAUUCUUUUCUAAGUAAUAACAUCAAUGGUUAAAUGCUUCAAAAUUAAGUUCUUUAUGAUUUUGGUAGUGUUUUCCAUUUUGAUGAAAUACAAAUGUGAAAUUUUUCAGGUUUAUCAUAUUUAGGUACCAUAUGUGAUCCUUUACAAAGCUGCUUUAUUAAUGAAGAAAAAGGACUCAUUUCUGCUUUUACUAUAGCCCAUGAGCUUGGGCACACGUAAGUACCUUCUGUCACCUCCUUAAUGUGCAUUCUAUUUAUCUUUGCACAGAAUGCCUGAAAUUCUAUCUUCAGUUGAGUAAUUAGUACCUUUGUUUCUUCAUAAAAUGUUAUUAGUGUAAUUUUCUUCCCUGAAAUGCUAACUCUGGCUCUUUUGUGAUCUAUGUUAGGUCAGACAGGCUGCACAGAUCAACAGACUAAGCAAAGAACUAGAACUUGGGAGUUCUUUUAUUUCCUUUACUGUAUUGGAUACAUGACAAGCACUUCUGGCCUCUGUCUCUUGUUAUCCUAUAUAUGACCAGACUUGGUGUUCAACAUGAUGAUAAUCCUAGAUGUAAAGAAAUGAAAGUUACAAAGUAUCAUGUAAUGGCCCCUGCUUUAAGUUUUCACAUGAGUCCUUGGAGCUGGUCAAACUGUAGUCGGAAAUAUGUUACUGAAUUCCUAGAUACUGGUUACGGGGAAUGUCUUCUUGACAAACCAGAUGAAGAAAUAUAUAAUCUGCCUUCAGAACUUCCUGGAUCACGAUAUGAUGGAAACAAGCAGUGUGAGCUUGCGUUUGGUCCUGGGUCACAAAUGUGUCCCCAUAUAGAGAAUAUAUGCAUGCAUCUGUGGUGCACAAGCACAGAAAAGCUUCACAAAGGCUGUUUCACUCAACACGUGCCACCAGCAGAUGGAACAGACUGCGGUCCUGGAAUGCAUUGCCGUCAUGGGCUAUGUGUAAACAAAGAAACGGAAACACGUCCUGUAAAUGGUGAAUGGGGACCAUGGGAACCUUACAGUUCUUGUUCAAGAACAUGUGGAGGCGGAAUCGAAAGUGCAACCAGGCGCUGUAAUCGUCCUGAGCCAAGAAACGGAGGAAAUUACUGUGUGGGCCGCAGGAUGAAAUUUCGAUCAUGUAAUACUGAUUCAUGUCCAAAAGGCACACAAGACUUUCGAGAGAAGCAGUGCUCUGAUUUUAAUGGUAAACAUUUGGACAUCAGUGGCAUUCCCUCUAAUGUGAGGUGGCUUCCAAGAUACAGUGGCAUUGGCACAAAGGAUCGUUGUAAACUCUAUUGUCAGGUUGCUGGAACCAAUUAUUUCUACCUAUUGAAGGAUAUGGUUGAAGAUGGUACUCCUUGUGGAACUGAAACUCAUGACAUCUGUGUUCAAGGCCAGUGUAUGGCAGCUGGUUGUGAUCACGUGUUAAACUCCAGUGCCAAGAUAGACAAAUGUGGAGUGUGUGGUGGGGACAACUCUUCAUGCAAGACAAUAACAGGUGUCUUCAACAGUUCUCAUUAUGGUUAUAAUGUUGUUGUAAAGAUUCCCGCAGGAGCAACAAACGUUGACAUUCGUCAGUACAGCUAUUCUGGACAACCAGAUGACAGUUACCUUGCAUUAUCUGACGCUGAAGGGAAUUUUCUUUUCAAUGGAAAUUUUCUUCUAAGUACGUCAAAAAAAGAAAUCAAUGUGCAAGGAACAAGAACUGUUAUUGAAUACAGUGGAUCAAAUAACGCAGUUGAAAGAAUUAAUAGUACUAAUCGACAAGAGAAAGAACUUAUUUUGCAGGUGUUGUGUGUGGGUAAUUUAUACAACCCUGAUGUACAUUAUUCCUUCAAUAUCCCUUUGGAAGAGAGGAGUGACAUGUUCACAUGGGACCCCUAUGGACCAUGGGAAGGCUGUACCAAAAUGUGUCAAGGUCUUCAGCGAAGAAACAUAACUUGCAUACAUAAGAGUGAUCAUAGUGUUGUGUCUGAUAAAGAAUGUGACCACUUGCCACUUCCAUCAUUUGUUACUCAAAGUUGCAAUACAGACUGUGAACUAAGGUGGCAUGUUAUUGGCAAAAGUGAAUGUUCAUCCCAAUGUGGUCAAGGAUAUAGAACCUUGGACAUCCAUUGCAUGAAGUAUUCCAUUCAUGAAGGACAGACUGUUCAAGUUGAUGACCACUACUGUGGUGACCAGCUUAAACCUCCUACCCAAGAACUAUGCCAUGGUAACUGUGUCUUCACAAGAUGGCAUUAUUCAGAAUGGUCUCAGUGUUCCAGGAGUUGUGGAGGAGGGGAAAGGUCUCGAGAAUCUUAUUGUAUGAAUAACUUUGGCCAUCGUCUUGCUGACAAUGAAUGCCAAGAACUGUCCCGAGUGACGAGAGAGAAUUGCAAUGAAUUUUCCUGUCCCAGUUGGGCUGCUAGUGAAUGGAGCGAGUGCCUUGUUACAUGUGGUAAAGGAACAAAGCAGCGGCAGGUAUGGUGUCAGCUGAAUGUAGAUCACUUGAGUGAUGGCUUCUGUAAUUCAAGUACCAAACCUGAAUCUCUGAGUCCAUGUGAACUUCAUACAUGUGCUUCCUGGCAAGUAGGACCAUGGGGUCCUUGCACAACCACAUGUGGACAUGGGUAUCAGAUGCGAGAUGUUAAAUGUGUCAAUGAGCUAGCUAGUGCAGUGUUAGAGGACACAGAAUGCCAUGAAGCUAGUCGCCCCAGUGACAGACAGAGCUGUGUACUUACACCUUGCUCAUUUAUUUCUAAACUUGAGACCGCUUUAUUACCAACUGUUCUCAUAAAAAAGAUGGCACAAUGGCGACAUGGUUCUUGGACCCCAUGCUCCGUAUCUUGUGGAAGAGGUACUCAAGCCCGCUAUGUAAGCUGUCGUGAUGCUCUUGAUAGAAUAGCAGAUGAAUCAUAUUGUGCCCACUUACCCCGACCUGCUGAAAUAUGGGACUGUUUUACCCCUUGUGGAGAGUGGCAAGCAGGGGAUUGGUCACCCUGUUCAGCUUCCUGUGGCCAUGGAAAAACAACUCGACAAGUUUUAUGCAUGAACUACCAUCAGCCAAUUGAUGAGAAUUACUGUGAUCCUGAAGUUCGCCCUUUGAUGGAACAGGAAUGUAGCCUGGCAGCCUGCCCUCCUGCACACAGCCACUUUCCUAGUUCCCCUGUGCAGCCAAGCUAUUAUCUAAGCACGAAUUUGCCAUUAACUCAAAAACUUGAAGAUAAUGAAAAUCAGGUGGUCCAUCCAUCAGUCAGAGGAAACCAGUGGAGAACCGGACCAUGGGGAUCAUGCUCCAGCAGUUGUUCUGGAGGUCUUCAGCAUAGGGCUGUGGUCUGCCAGGAUGAAAAUGGACAAAGUGCUAGUUACUGCGAUGCAGCCUCCAAGCCUCCAGAGUUACAGCAAUGUGGUCCAGGGCCUUGUCCACAGUGGAACUACGGAAAUUGGGGAGAAUGUUCACAAACAUGUGGAGGAGGAAUAAAAUCAAGACUUGUAAUAUGUCAAUUUCCCAAUGGCCAAAUAUUAGAAGAUCACAACUGUGAAAUUGUAAACAAGCCACCUAGCGUAAUACAGUGUCAUAUGCAUGCUUGCCCUGCUGAUGUGUCAUGGCAUCAGGAACCAUGGACAUCGUGCUCAGCUUCUUGUGGUAAAGGUAGAAAGUACCGUGAAGUGUUUUGCAUUGACCAAUUCCAAAGGAAAUUAGAAGACACAAAUUGCAGUCAAGUACAGAAACCUCCAACUCACAAAGCCUGUAGAUCUGUCAGAUGCCCUUCAUGGAAAGCCAAUAGCUGGAAUGAGUGCUCUGUGACCUGUGGCUCUGGAGUUCAGCAGAGGGAUGUAUACUGCAGACUGAAAGGUGUUGGUCAGGUGGUUGAAGAAAUGUGUGAUCAGUCCACCCGACCUUGUUCUCAGAGGCGAUGUUGGAGUCAGGACUGUGUGCAGCACAAGGGGAUGGAAAGAGGGAGGCUGAAUUGUUCAACAUCAUGUGAGAGAAAAGAUUCACAUCAACGAAUGGAGUGCACAGAUAACCAAAUCAGACAAGUGAAUGAAAUAGUCUAUAAUUCUUCAACCAUAUCUCUUACAUCCAAGAAUUGCAGGAACCCUCCUUGCAAUUACAUUGUGGUAACAGCAGACUCAUCACAGUGUGCAAACAACUGUGGAUUUAGUUACAGACAAAGGAUUACAUAUUGCACCGAGAUCCCAUCUACUAAGAAACAUAAGCUCCAUCGACUUCGGCCUAUAGUUUAUCAAGAAUGCCCUGUGGUGCCUUCCUCUCAGGUUUACCAAUGCAUUAACAGCUGUUUGCAUUUGGCCACUUGGAAAGUUGGAAAAUGGAGCAAGUGCUCAGUGACUUGUGGAAUUGGGAUAAUGAAGAGACAAGUGAAAUGCAUUACCAAACAUGGUUUGUCCAGUGACUUAUGUUUAAACCAUUUAAAACCAGGUGCUCAAAAGAAAUGUUAUGCCAAUGACUGUAAAUCAUUUACCACCUGCAAAGAAAUUCAAGUGAAAAACCACAUUAGAAAGGAUGGUGACUAUUACCUUAACAUUAAGGGAAGAAUAAUAAAGAUUUAUUGUGCAGACAUGUACUUGGAGAACCCUAAGGAAUAUUUAACACUGGUCCAAGGUGAAGAAAACUUUUCUGAAGUGUAUGGCUUUAGACUAAAAAAUCCAUAUCAAUGUCCUUUUAAUGGGAGUAGAAGGGAAGACUGUGAAUGUGACAAUGGACACUUAGCUGCUGGAUACACUGUUUUCAGCAAAAUAAGAAUUGAUCUCACUUCCAUGCAAAUUAAAACUACGGACCUUCUUUUUUCCAAAACAAUAUUUGGAAAUGCAGUUCCAUUUGCCACAGCUGGAGAUUGCUACAGUGCUUUCAGAUGCCCACAGGGACAGUUUAGCAUUAAUUUGUCAGGAACUGGGAUGAAGAUAUCCAGCACAGCAAAGUGGCUCACUCAGGGGAGUUAUACCUCUGUCAGCAUACGAAGAUCAGAGGAUGGAACUAGAUUUUUCGGCAAAUGUGGAGGGUACUGUGGAAAGUGUCUUCCUCACAUGACUACUGGUCUCCCAAUUCAAGUCAUAUGAACAUUUAGAAGGGGGAAGUAUGCCCUAAAGAGGGGAUAUUCUCUGGAAUAUUCAAAUAACUGGUGCUCAUUUCUUUAUAUCUCCCUUCCCGAGAUUUCCAUGUCCAAUAUGUCUCUGCCUUUUUUUCAGGGUGCUCAUCAGGGAUUCAAAUCACUGCUUAAUAAGGUCUAUAAAAGAAAUUUAAGAGCUAUCUUAAUUUAUUUUAUAUCUAAUCAGGAUAUUUUUUAAAGAACAUAAUAAUUUAUAAUAGAGAAUACCAGGAUUGAAUGAAUUAUACCAAGACAGUGUUGCUCUUAACAUCUUGGCCUGGACCACACUUAUUUUAUACCUAUAAACACACAUGUAAAUCUCUGCUCAGUUUUGUACUGUACAAUGAAAUGUUUAUUCUACUUGCUAAAAUGAAGCAAGUAAAUAUUAGGAUAAUAAACAUUCAAAAUUACUAUAAACAUUAUUGAAUCUUUCCGACAAAUAGCAAAUCAAUAGUUACAUAAAAAAGCACAGAGCCAUUGUACUUUGUACUCAUACAGUUUAGAUACCUUCUUUUAUUUUUUCUUUAAUUUUUGCUUGUGGAUUAUGGGGCUUCAAUUAAAAAAUAGUCCUCAAAAUGAGGUACAAAUUGUGUAUUAAAAAGGUAUGUUUGGGUUAAAUAGUAAAUAAAAAAUUUUGUGGGUAUAAUAAAGAUAUGAUAUAAUUUAAUUUUUAAAAUCUACCUCAAAUUUGAUUGUACUUAUAAGAACAAUACAUUGUUUUUAUAAUGUUAAUAUUCUGUUUUGCCUUUAUAAUUCUUGUAUGUGUAUAUAUAUUCUUUAAAAAUCUAUUUUCUCAAAGUUAUGUACUGUAUUCUAUUAAUUAAAUAUGUGAGAAUUCUUUUAAUUUUGAAGAUCUUAUUUUGGUAAACAUAAAAAUAUAUUGGCAUAUGUAAAAGUUUUAUUAGAGAUGUUUAAGUUAUUUUAUAUCAGAGGUUUCUCAAAGCCAGAACAUAAGGGAGUAUAAAAAUUAACUAUUAAUUGGCAAAUUCUCAGGUAUUGAGUUUUUUUCAUGCAGAUAAUUUAACCAUGUAUUAUAUAAUAAUAUACUUUUGAAAGACAUGUAGACAAAUAUAUUUUUCUAUGGAAAUCUACUCGGAAAACCAAAAAAAACCAAAUGGAAUCUACUAAUAGAUUUUUGCCAGUGAAUACUAGUGUACUUUUUUUACCCACAAAGUGUUUUUCUCCCAAACAUUUAUUACAGAUGUAUUGUACCAUAUAAAGCUCUAAUACAAUUUUGUUUCAAUGUGGUUAAACAUUUGAAGAUGUCUGUAUCAAAAGAAAUAUUUUGUAUUAUGUGCCUUAAGCCAGUUACAAACAUUAAGACAAAAUGUGUGACAUUUUCCAGGAAUCUUUUCAUGUAUAUUUAGAAUCUUACAAUUGAUAAACAUUUAAAUAAACAUAUUUUUAUGAUUCAUUA